CUCUCUCUCUCGGCUGCUGCCAUGUGAGACGUGCCUUUCAUCUUCUGCCAUGAUUGUGAGGCCUCCCCAGCCAUGUGGAACUGUAAGUCCAAUAAACCUCUUUCUUUUGUAAGUUGCCCAGUCUCGGGUAUGUCUUUAUCAGCAUUGUGAAAACGGACUAAUACAAAUGCCUCUCUCACAGCUCUGUGGGCCAGAAGUCUGAAAUGAAUCUCACUGAGCCAAGAUCAAGGGUGGACAGGGCUGUGCUCCCUCCAGAGGCUCCAGGGGAGAAUCUGUUUCUGGCCCAUCCCCGCUCCUGGGGGCUGCCAGCCUCCCUUGGCUUGUGGCUGCAUCAUGCCAAUCUCUGCCCCCGGGUCAUGUCGCCCCCUCCUCUUCUGACGUGUCCCUGUGCUUCCCUCUUGCAAGGAUGCCUUGAUUACAUUUAGGACUCACCCGAGUAAUCCAGGACAGGCUUCUCAUCUCAAGAGCCUUACUGCAAGCACAUCUGCAAAGCCCUUUCUUCCCAUAGAAGGUACCCGUCUCAGGUUGCAGGGAUCAGGAUCCAGCAUCUUUGGGGGCACCAUGCAGCCAGCUACAGGAUGUGAAUGGCCCUCACGUACAAGGCUGGCCACGCAGUGCACAGCACACCCGGGAGGCGCCCGUCUGGGUCACGCGGAGGAGCAGCACUGUAGGCUUCACUUAGGCCUCCCCAGGGCAUAUAGCCCAGAGGCACAGCCCAGGCAGGCCCUGGUCCUGCUGCCUCCCUCACUGGACCCUCCACCCUGUCGUGUGGGAGCUCUUCCCUGCAUGUCUAAGUGCCAGUCUCAGCCUGGCAGUCCUCCCCCACCGCCCGCGUUAAGGGACCUGGAGCGGCUGACUCCAAGACCACGUGCACAGAGAAGCCAACCCUGUGCUGACACUGAGGGCCUGUCUUAGCUUCCCAGAGACUGACCUUGGGACUCUGUGAAGGUUGCCACACAGUGAGAAAGACCCCGAGUCACGUGUUGAGCAUGUGGUCUCUGUUUCAGACACACAGUGCCAUUUGCAGAAAGACAAGAGCUGCAAACUCAGAGCCUGCAGGGCCUGGCAGGCAAUGCCAACAAGGACAGCAGUGGAGGAAAAAAAGAUAAUUGCACCCACCCUUGGCCUGGCUUUCAUUUCUCUCCUUUUGAUGGAAACGUGGAGACCAAGAAUACAUCUCCACUAAAAAGAAACAGCAGUGGGAAUGCAGCCACACGUGGUGUCCAGCCCUGGCCUUGCCAUGGGCACAGGGCGUCUGGGAGGCCCUGCAAGGAGGGACAGACCCUCCUCAACUCCCUUGACCUCAAUUUGGUAGAAGUUGGGUCUGGUGCAGCUGAACAUCCUAUCAAGAAAAUCCAGACAUCAGACUUUUUAUGUGAACUUUCCUGAUGUUAAAAUGUGGCUUAAAAUUUCUGGAAUGAGAGGAUGAACUGAGAAGGCUCCAGGAAUCCAGCCACGGCGCUGAGCUCAGUGAGUCGGCAACAGCUGGCUUGGCAGGGCCCAGGCCGACCCGGGUACGAGAGACAGCCCCUAUCACCAUGCGAAAGGACCAGGCCUCAGGGGUCUGGGGAGUCACUCAGGAAGUGCCUGGUUGGAGACACAGAGACAGGUCCUGGCACAAGGACGCUGGCCAGGUCCAGGGCUCAGCCAGCAAAUCCAGACAAAGCCCUCUUUCCACAGAAGCCUCCACAUCAGCUCUCUGCCUCCAGCCCUGGGCCCUGCACACCCAGUGGGAGCUGUCAUGCCUGGGGUCCCCUCCCGUGCUCACUAUAUAGACCAAACAAAACACGGUCCCCCAUUGGCUACCCAUGCUUUCUGUGAUGCAGAGGUAGAAGCAUCUUCUGCCCUCCUCUGUGGGCUGCUCUCCUGGGGCUCGCCCCGGCCUGGCCUUGGGACAGAGGAGGGGCAGGUGCUUCCCAUCCUGGGGAACUGCUACCAGGCUGCUGUGCACACACCCUGCUGGGCUGAAGGAAGAGAAGUCAGACAGCAACGUGCCAGUGACCUUGGCUGCCUCCACCCCAGACACCGCCGGUGCCAAGCCUCUGCCUGCUGCUGUCAGGCUGCAGCAUCCUCCCUGACGGGCAGACGAGGCACGCCACCACGGGAGCCUCUCAGCCUCGCUGCACCAAGGAAGGCCCUCCAGGAGACAGAGGACAAGCGCCGGCACUGGGCAGCUCCUCCAUGUGGCUGAGCGUGGCUGCCACCUGCAGCCCACAGCCAGCCCUUCCCCACCAGGCCAGGAAGAGCCCCUCCUGACCCACAGUCUCCACCCUGUGACUUUGCCUUGAGUUGGGUAGGAGUUUUCCAGGCCGCAGGGGAUCCUGGGGGAAGAGUGGGCGGCGGGGGUGGGGGCGGACCUCAGGCAUGACAGUUCCCCCUGGGUGUGCAGAGCCCAGGGCUGGAGGCAGAGAGCUGUGGGGCAGCCUCCAUGGAAGCAGCAGCCUUGAAUGACCCAAGGUGGGGAUGGCGCCCUCCAGUCUCACAAAGAGUUGAGUGUUUCAGCAAGCUCGUACUGGUUGCAGUGUGAGGGAGGCUGGUGGGGGAGGCUGGAGCAAUGGCACAGGAGAGAGAGAGGAGCUCUGUUCUGUCAGACCACAGGACUGGGGAGCAGGCGAGACUCAUCCAUUCAGUGGCGAGCAGAUAGCCAGCCCCACUGACACAGCGGAUGUGAGGCUUGGCCCAGGUGGGGGCUGGGGGGCCCAGGAUGGGGCAGGAGGGCCGUGUGCUUUGUUGGGGGGUGCCAAUUUGCUGAAUGCCAGGUCAGAGAGCCUUUCUGCCCUGUAGCUGUCGACGUCCAUCUCAGCUUCCUGUGGCUGCUGUACCAGGUUACCCACACCUUAAUGGCUUAAAACAGCACACCUGCAUUCCUCACAGUUCGGGAGCUCAGAACUCUGAAAUAGGAUUUUAGGGGCUAAGAUCAAGGUGCUGGCAGGGCUGGUUCCUUCGGGAGGCCCCAGGGCAGAAUCCAUUCCUGGCCCCUCCCAGCUCCUGGGGGCUGUUGGCGUUCCUUGGCUUGUGGCAACAUUGCUGCAGUCUCUGCCUCCCUGGUCACGUGGCUUCUCCUCUUCUAUAGCCAGCUCUCCCUCUUAGAAGGACACUUGUGAUAACAUUUAGGGCCCGCUGGGACCAUCCAGGUUACUUUCCCCAUCUCAAGACCCCUGAUUUAAACACAUUUGCAAAGUCUCUUCUGCCAUAUAAGGUAAUGCUCACGAGUUUUGGGGGAUUAGGACAUGGACGUCCGGGGGUCAUGAUUCAGCUGACAUGUCUAAGUGUUGAACCUUGGGUCCUAAGGGAGAAUGGAGAGAGGGCUUUGGCUGGAUUUGCAGGGUGAGCCCUGGACCUGGCCAGCGUCUUGUGCCCAGACCUGUCUCUGUGUCUCCAACCGGGCACUUCCCAAGUGACUCCCCAGACCCCUGAGGCCAGGGCCUCUGGCGUGGUGAUAGGUGCUCUCUCUCAUACCCUGGUCAGCCUGGGCCCUGCCAAGCCACUGUUGCCGACUCACUGAGUUCAGCGCCUCGGCGCUGGAUCCCUGGAGUCUUCUCAGCUCAUCCUCUCUUUCCACCCUGGAGCUGAGCCUGCAGCCCAGGCCCCGGGAAACCCAGGGAGAAGCACUGAUUGUGAAACCCGAGGCGGCUCCGGGAGGCGUGCUUCAGGGCUGAGCGCACCCUUGGCAGACGCCGCGGCGCUCCUGUCCUCGUGCAGACCGGGCCCUUGGGAUGGCUGUUGGAGAUGCCAGCGCGGUGAUGUGGCCCACGCGGAAGGGGUGGGCGGGGGCCGGCGCUGGGAAAGCCGAGGCUGCACAUUCUCCGAGGCUGGAGUUGCCUGGGGUCAGCCGGGGAGAGCAGGAGGGGCCAGCUCCCGGGCCUGGCUGGCUCUCUGGCUGGAGUCUGCUGCUCAGAGCGCUGCCCUGUGGGUGCUUCCCACCCCCUGGGCUGUGAAGGCAGAAGCGAGGCUUGCAGCCCCAGCGAGGGCUGGGCCCCCCUUAUUCCACAGUGGAGACGUGCCAGGGUGUGCUCCCCCUCCACGGCGUCUGGGCCUGGCACUCCGCCUGACAGCCCCCACGUGCGCAGCAACUCCCCUGUGCCUCCGACAUAAAUUUAGUCCCUGAGUCUCAGGCUUGCCCUUCCCCCGCCACCUCUCCCCUCCCGACAUGGUUUCUGGUUCAGGGGUGGAGCCGACCAGGUAAAUGUGGCUGGCAAGGGCCUGGAUCUUUGGUGGAGCACCGUGGGCAGGUGACAAGCCUGACCCGGAGGAUGGUGGCCUUGGCCCUGGCUUGGCUGCAGCCCCAACUCGAGUGCAGGGGACAGUUCUGGAAGACCGGCCAGUGGUUCUGAGGAGCUGCAUUAGGGCUGCUCCCACAGAUGCUUCCAGCACUAGGUGGGUGAGUGGGGUGGGCAGCGGGCAGUUUGGUGCAGGGUUCAGUGUGCUCAGCCCCACCCGGCAUGCUGCUGUUGGUGCAGGGGUCAGUGUGCUCAGCCCCGCCCGGCAUGCUGCUGUUGGUGCAGGGGUCAGCGCUGGUGCAGGGGUCAGCGCGCUCAGCUCCGCCCAGCAUGCUGCUGUUGGUGCAGGGGUCAGUGUGCUCAGCUCCACCCGACAUGCUGUUGUUCUGGCUCACUAAGGGGCCCAGAGCAGCUCACCCAGCCCCUCAGGAUCUCAGAACCUGGGUGCUGAGAUCUCCACUGUACCUGGGUGCAGUGGCACAGGGGCUGCUGGAAUUACGCAGGGCACAGGGCGCCUGCCCAGUGCUCACUGCGACACUUGCUCUCCGUCCCCUUUCCCUCCUCUGCCUCGCCAUCUUCCACAGACACAGUGAAUUGAUACUUUCUUUCCUUCCCUUGGAUCUGUGUUGGGAAUGUCCUCCAAAGAGCUUUUCGGGUUUUGCACAAGGUAACAGUCCCUGGCAUGCAGACAGUACACGGCUCAGGGGUGAAGCUGUGAUCUGCUCACGGGGGCAUCUGGCGUUUGAUCAGCAACUGUGGGCUGGGCAUGCCCCCUCUUUUCAGGUCCCCAGCAUGGCAGAGGCAGGCUUCUGGGAGAGAGGCAUGUGUCCAGGGCAUCUUUUCAUGUCUGUGACAUCUGUGCCUUGGAUGUAGGAGCCUGCUGGCUGGGGUGAAGUUUGGGCAAGGAGCAGUGGGACCUGCUUGGGACCCAGGUGAGGCUUCCUUCAUGCCCUGGCUGCCCCAUGGAUGACGGUGAAAGAGACAUGGGCACCCUGCAUAAUGGGGACAAAGGGACUGCAUCCCAUAGUGGGUCCCUAGACAGAGGCCUCUUGGGGAUAGAGAGGGGUGGGGCGACAGGUGAGAGGCGUUGGGUACCAGCAUCAGGGCUGCAGAGGCAGCUGUAGGGACAUCUGAAGGGGACAGGAAGCUCUUCCCCAGCAGCAGCGAGGACAGGCCUGGCUCAGAAACUGCAUUUGGGUCCGAGGUCCAAACUCUGCCAGUUUGUGCCAGCCGGAGGCCUCUGACCACAGGCCCCAUCUCCUCUCAGAAUUCUCUGCAGGUUGGCAGACACUUCAGCCAGCUCCAAGCCUGAAAUAUUUUCUAUAAAAAUUUCCAAUUUUCUUUGACCCGUUUCUCUUUGAAAUUAAUCCUAGGCAGCGCUGUGCUCUGGGCCCUGAAGGAGCUCUGAGCGGGGAAAGGUCGCGCAGUCAGAUGGGCGUGCUGGCGUCUGUCUUCUCUCUCUCCUGCUCUCUGGCUUCAUUUUUCUCUCCUUCUGUCUCACCUUCUUUCGUGUGCCUGUGCACACACACGUUUGGGACAAGGGCUGGAUUCUUCGGCUGGGAUGUCUCUCAGAGCUCUUGACUUGGUCCCUUUGGCUGGGGCUUGCCGUGAGGUGUGGGCUGCGCCACGAGCACAGCUGGUAGAGAACCCGGCCAGGAGCGCAGCUCACGCCUCCCACGCCUCCCAUCCCAAACUGUCGGCACACCCAGAGAGAGCCUGCAGGACAGGACAGGAGGUGACCUGGGCACUGGGCCUGUGUGGAGAGGUGGCUGGUGCGCUGGUCUGGUUGGGAAAAGGCCGGGCACCUGAAUGCCAUGCGGGUUCAUUAAUGCUCAAUAAUAAUGCUGCUCCCCAAAUCAUGGGGGAAUAAUGCUGCUCCCCAAAUCAUGGGGGAAUAAUGCUGCUCCCCAAAUCAUGGGGGAAUAAUACUGCUCCCCAAAUCAUGGGGGAAUAAUGCUGCUCCCCAAAUCAUGGGGGAAUAAUGCUGCUCCCCAAAUCAUGGGGGAAUAAUGCUGCUCCCCAAAUCAUGGGGGAAUAAUGCUGCUCCCCAAAUCAUGGGGGAAUAAUGCUGCUCCCCAAAUCAUGGGGGAAUAAUGCUGCUCCCCAAAUCAUGGGGGAAUAAUGCUGCUCCCCAAAUCAUGGGGGAAUAAUGCUGCUCCCCAAAUCAUGGGGGAAUAAUGCUGCUCCCCAAAUCAUGGGGGAAUAAUACUGCUCCCCAAAUCAUGGGGGAAUAAUACUGCUCCCCAAAUCAUGGGGGAAUAAUAGCAUUAGCAGCUCUACUGCUUAGGGGGAGACUGAGGCUCAGAGAGGGCACCUUGCCUGCUGCCACAAGUGUAUUUUCCUGCAUUCACUCGUCACGUUCUUGCUAUGUGUCCACCAUGUGUCUGACAGGACUGGGUGCUGGGGCUGUAGCAGCGGAGGAACCCGAUCGAGUCCCUGUUCUCUGGGCUCACAGCCCCGCAGGGGAGACCUGGUGAGCAGAUGCUCGCAGACAGUGGAGAAUCCUGUGAACAAAGUAAAACGGGGUGAAAGGGCAGCGUGAGAAGGCAGGUAAGGGAGGGAGGCGCCCCAGGUUGGUGAUGAUGGGAAAGCCCAGCCCUGGGAAGGGUGUUCCAGGCAGAGGGAACAGCACAUGCAGGAGCCCUGAGGCUGGAGUUACCGCAGCGUGACCAAGGGGCAGAAGGAAGAGCUAGUACCUGGAACUGAGGACGUAAUGGGGGAGUGGGAGGCGUGCAGGGCCGGGAGGGAUGGGUGGCACUCAUCGCUUUGAAGGGACGGUCACGGUACGGGGUGAGAAUUCAUUCCCUGUGCGGUGGAGGCCUUUGGAGGGUUUUCGGUGGACGGUGUGGAAGCAGGGAGGAGUCCCGGUGACAGAUGGCGGUGGAGGCAGUGGGUUCAGGAUGAGUUUGAGGUGGAGCUUCCGGGACGUGGUGUGAAGGAAGGAAUCAAGGACACAUCCUGCCCCUGAGAGGUCACGUGGCUGGGAGGCUGGCUGGUGGCCUGAGGCUGGCCGGGCAGGUGUGCUGGUGGGGGUGGCCGGGCAGGUGUGCUGGUGGGGGUGGCAGGUUAGGUGGUCUGGGCCACGUGCAGGAGUCAGAAUUGGCACCCAUCACUCUGACUCCACAGCUGCCCGCUUCCACUGCUCUGCACUGCCCUGGCCCAGAGGGAGGUGUUUUCCCAGGAAAGAAGGUGCCAAGGCCAAGACCCAUGUGUUCCCAGACUCACGGGGCGGGGGCAGGAGCCCCCAAUGCAGCCCCACAGGCAGCCAGGCCCUGGGAUGCACUGCCACCUCCUCUUGCUCCGGGAGGCAGAGGCUGUGCUCUGUGGGGCGGGCUGUCAGGGACAGUGUGAGGUUUGGGGUCCCAUGGACGUGUGUGCAUCCUUGUUUGUCUAGCAGGACCGGUCCAGCUUCCCCUUGCCUGCCACUGUGGGGAGGGACCCCAGACUGGCCGGGAUGAAUGGAUGCAGGAACUGUGGCCUGCACGUACUUAGGAGUGUGCAGGGCAGGGUGUGUGGCUGCCUCUAGGCCUUUGCAGGCAGAGCCUUCCUGUCCACCCCAAGGGGCCGCAGGCAGCGCUACCAGCUGUUCCCCACACAAAAGCUGCCCGAGACAGCUGGAAUGCUCCCUGCUCCUGGUGCAAACUCUCUUGAAACUCAGGGGUGGGGACAUCCUGGGAGCUGACCUCAGGUUCUGUUCCUGCAAAUAGGUAUCUGUUGCUGACCCGGCAGAUGGCGGCCUGAGCCAGCCCAGACGCGCUCGAGCCCUGGCCCUGAGCAGCCAUCAGGGGGCACCUACUGAGUGACUAAAUGAAUUAGGAAAUCCCAGCGCUUAACAGACUCACCACUCGGGGCAGAGCCAGACUGGCUCCCACAGCAGCUCCUGGUUUCUCCAAAUCCUCACCAGCACGGGGGCUUUAGUGUUUAAUAUUUUGCUGCUCCGGCAGCAAAGCGGCGUUGCUUUUUGCGCUAAUUUGCGCUUCUUUGGUUACUGGCGAGGAUGAGUGAUCUUCCCUGGGUUUGAUUACUCUGCAUGUCUCCUAUUCCUAAGUCCUUUGCCUGUUUAUCUCCUGGGGUCUUAUAUAUUGGGAUAAGCCCUUUAUCUCUUUUUAGAUAUUGACUUUCUGUCAUGUUCGAUACAAGCUUUUCCCCAGGCCGUAGUUCCUCUUUCCUUUCCAGUUUUGUUAGCGUUAGUUGCACAAAAGUCUGUUUUUCUGUAGCUGAGUCUGAAUGAUCCUUCUCCUGCCCCGUUGGAGCCAAGUUUGCGUUCAAGGACAUGCCCAUUCACCGAGGGCCUGCGCGAAGGUGGGCACUCUUCAUGGUGUCAUUUAAUAGGCACGGUAGUCCUGGAAGCAGAGAGAAAACUAAGGUGCAGGGCUACCACUGUCCAAGCAGUAGCGGGAACAGCAGGGAGCAAGAAGAACGUGACGCGUUCCUGGAGCACUUACCGUUGACCGCGUCUGCCAGCACGCUGCAGGUACAUCAUCUCCUAGGAUUCUUGUAAUGAGCCCCACGGUGGGUUGGUGCUUUUGCUGUGCCCACGUUACAGAUGAGGAAACUGAGGUGCCGACGGUCGCACAGAUAGUAAGCUGUAGAAACAGUGGGAGCCAGGCCUUUUGACUCCUGCAUCAGGAGGGAGGAGCAGGCUUAGAACCCAGGGCUGCUGACACCCAGUGCAGUGCCCUCCUGUCCCCGCUCAGAGCCUGGGCUGGCAAAACCCGGUAGCCUGUGACCCCAUCUGUUUGUUGGACAGAGGGCCUUCCAAGCACCAAGGCCUGGAACUCCACUUAACGGCUGCAGAAACUGGGGCCCAGCGAGGGUGAGUGAGGAUGUGUCUCCAGGUCACUUAGCACGUUAGCUUCGGGGAGAAUCUUUUGCUUACAGUGGAAUUUGCAGCAUUUUGAGGAAUGCCUGGCACACGGUUGGUGCGUAAAUAUCCGUGAAAAGAAAGAAUAAGCAUAGUGCCUAGGAAGCCCGGUCGCCCAGGAGCUCACUCCGGGAGCAACAGUUGCUCCCUGCAGGCAUUGGAGGGCUUGGCACUGACGCCUCCUGUUGUUGCCACAGUGUCAGGGCUGCAGACUCAGGUUGGCAGCUGUGGGUGGCUACUGGUCCCAUGGGCCCAUGGGACAUUGGGUGGCCCUGGGCCUUUGCUAGUCCCACUUCCUCACACUUGAGCAGGACUGACUUCGCCGGCUUGUGACCCAUCCGGCAGGGCCCUAUGCCCACUUUAACACUCUGUCAUUCCUGCCUUAGAAGUCGUAAUCACUUUUUGAACAAGGGACUGUGCGUUUCCAUUUUGCACUGUGCCCUGCAAAUCAAGUGGCCAGUGCUGUUCAUCACUCUUUCUUCUGUGACUCUGCUUCCUCCCUGUGGUCUCAUGGAGCUGUGGUCCAGGCCCCGAGGUUGAGGACACAGGGCACUGCACAGUGGCCAAAAUUGGGGGUGCCCAGUAGACACGGGCUCCCUUCCUUCCAGGCCCAAGCACCAGCACUUUCUGACAGUUAACUGUCUGUCCUUUAUUUGGGAAUGUCUGAUGCCAGACUGCAGAUGGCGAGGAAGAUGGCCCUGUCCAUGCUGGAACGACAGACCCGGUAUCAGGAAUGUGCCCCUGUGACUGCCACAGGCCUGUUUGGUGCCUGAGGGCAGCAAUGCGUGAAUCCCAGCCUCUGCCCUGGGGAUGCCGUCGGGCUGGAGCACUGCUCCCAGCGUGCCUUGGCCACUGUUCCCUGCGCGGUUGUCUCUGGACAUAAAGCACCUGUGGAAUCCCAGGGCUGCUCCCCUUCCUCUCUCCCUUGAUUCAUCCAACAGAUCUUUACCCGGCACGCACAGCAGGACCGGGCACUGGGCCAGGCUCUGGGACCAGACAGGCACAGCCCUGACCUCAUACAGCCCACAGUGCACUAGUCAGUCCACAAAUACCUGCACAAUGAAAGACUUGGGAAGUGCCACAGAGUGAGCCCGCAGUCACUGGACGUUGGGCUGAGGCCUGGAGUGUGGGUUGCAGUUCCCCAGGAGGAAAAGGGGCCAGGGCAGCAGAUGCGAAGUACCUGAGGGGGGCCUCCCUGGACAGCCUGGACAGCCUCAGCCGCGCCCUGGGCGUCCUAGAGGAGCACGCCAACAGCUCGAGGCGGAGGGCACGCAGGCAUGCUGCGGACGAUGACUACAACAUCGAGGUCCUGCUGGGCGUGGAUGACUCUGUGGUGCAGUUCCACGGGAAGGAGCACGUACAGAAGUACCUGCUGACACUCAUGAACAUUGUCAAUGAAAUCUACCAUGACGAGUCCUUGGGUGCCCACAUCAACGUGGUCCUGGUGCGGAUCAUCCUCCUGAGCUAUGGAAAGUCCAUGAGCCUCAUCGAGAUCGGGAACCCCUCUCAGAGCCUGGAGAAUGUCUGCCGCUGGGCCUACCUCCAGCAGAAGCCAGACACGGGCCACGAUGAAUACCACGAUCACGCCAUCUUCCUCACACGGCAGGACUUUGGGCCUUCCGGCAUGCAAGGCUAUGCUCCUGUCACCGGCAUGUGCCAUCCGGUCCGCAGCUGCACCCUGAACCAUGAGGACGGCUUCUCCUCAGCGUUUGUGGUGGCCCAUGAGACUGGCCACGUGCUGGGCAUGGAGCACGACGGGCAGGGCAACCGCUGUGGCGACGAGGUGCGGCUGGGCAGCAUCAUGGCGCCCCUGGUGCAGGCCGCCUUCCACCGCUUCCACUGGUCCCGCUGCAGCCAGCAGGAGCUGAGCCGCUACCUGCACUCCUAUGACUGCCUGCUGGAUGACCCCUUCGCCCACGACUGGCCGGCGCUGCCCCAGCUCCCGGGACUGCACUACUCCAUGAACGAGCAAUGCCGCUUUGACUUCGGCCUGGGCUACAUGAUGUGCACGGCGUUCCGGACCUUUGACCCCUGCAAGCAGCUGUGGUGCAGCCAUCCUGACAACCCCUACUUUUGCAAGACCAAGAAGGGGCCCCCCUUGGACGGGACUAUGUGUGCACCUGGCAAGCAUUGUUUUAAAGGACACUGCAUCUGGCUGACACCUGACAUCCUCAAACGGGACGGCAGCUGGGGCGCUUGGAGUCCGUUUGGCUCCUGCUCACGUACCUGUGGCACGGGCGUGAAGUUCAGGACCCGCCAGUGUGACAACCCACACCCGGCCAACGGGGGCCGCACCUGCUCGGGCCUUGCCUACGACUUCCAGCUCUGCAGCCGCCAGGACUGCCCCGACUCCCUGGCUGACUUCCGCGAGGAGCAGUGCCGCCAGUGGGACCUGUACUUCGAGCACGGCGACGCCCAGCACCACUGGCUGCCCCACGAGCACCGGGAUGCCAAGGAGAGAUGCCACCUGUACUGCGAGUCCAGGGAGACCGGGGAGGUGGUGUCCAUGAAGCGCAUGGUGCAUGACGGGACGCGCUGCUCCUACAAGGACGCCUUCAGCCUCUGUGUGCGCGGGGACUGCAGGAAGGUGGGCUGUGACGGUGUGAUCGGCUCCAGCAAGCAGGAAGACAAGUGUGGCGUGUGCGGAGGGGACAACAGCCACUGCAAAGUGGUCAAGGGCACGUUCACACGGUCACCCAAGAAGCAUGGUUACAUCAAGAUGUUUGAGAUCCCUGCAGGAGCCAGACACCUGCUCAUUCAGGAGGUAGACGCCACCAGCCACCAUCUGGCCGUCAAGAACCUGGAGACAGGCAAGUUCAUCUUAAAUGAAGAGAAUGACGUGGAUGCCAGUUCCAAAACCUUCAUUGCCAUGGGCGUGGAGUGGGAGUACAGAGACGAGGACGGCCGGGAGACGCUGCAGACCAUGGGCCCCCUCCACGGCACCAUCACCGUUCUGGUCAUCCCGGUGGGAGACACCCGGGUCUCACUGACGUACAAAUACAUGAUCCAUGAGGACUCACUGAAUGUCGACGACAACAACGUCCUGGAAGAGGACUCUGUGGUCUACGAGUGGGCCCUGAAGAAGUGGUCUCCGUGCUCCAAGCCCUGUGGCGGAGGGUCCCAGUUCACCAAGUAUGGCUGCCGCCGGAGGCUGGACCACAAGAUGGUACACCGUGGCUUCUGUGCCGCCCUCUCGAAGCCCAAAGCCAUCCGCAGAGCGUGCAACCCACAGGAAUGCUCCCAGCCAGUGUGGGUCACAGGCGAAUGGGAGCCAUGUAGCCAGACCUGUGGGCGGACAGGCAUGCAGGUGCGCUCCGUGCGCUGCAUUCAGCCGCUACACGACAACACCACCCGCUCCGUGCACGCCAAGCACUGCAAUGACGCCCGGCCCGAGAGCCGCCGGGCCUGCAGCCGCGAGCUCUGCCCUGGUCGUUGGCGAGCCGGGCCCUGGUCCCAGUGCUCAGUAACCUGUGGCAACGGCACCCAGGAGCGGCCAGUGCUCUGCCGCACCGCGGACGACAGCUUCGGCAUCUGCCAGGAGGAGCGUCCUGAGACAGCGAGGACCUGCAGGCUUGGCCCCUGUCCCCGAAACAUCUCAGAUCCCUCCAAGAAGAGCUACGUAGUUCAGUGGCUGUCCCGCCCGGACCCCGACUCGCCCAUCCGGAAGAUCUCGUCAAAGGGCCACUGCCAAGGCGACAAGUCAAUAUUCUGUAGGAUGGAAGUCUUGUCCCGCUAUUGCUCCAUCCCAGGCUACAACAAGCUGUGCUGCAAGUCCUGUAACCUGUACAACAACCUCACCAACGUGGAGGGCAGGAUAGAGCCACCGCCUGGGAAGCACAACGACAUUGACGUGUUCAUGCCUACCCUCCCAGUGCCCACUGUAGCCAUGGAGGUGCGGCCAUCACCAAGCACCCCCCUGGAGGUCCCUCUCAAUGCCUCCAGCACCAAUGCCACAGAGGAUCACCCAGAAACCAAUGCCGUAGAUGAACCCUACAAAAUCCAUGGCCUGGAAGAUGAAGUCCAGCCACCCAACCUAAUCCCUCGACGACCGAGCCCCUAUGAAAAGACCAGAAACCAAAGAAUCCAAGAGCUCAUUGAUGAGAUGCGGAAGAAAGAGAUGCUCGGAAAGUUCUAAUAAAAUGGAAAGAUAGCAUCCCUAGCAUUUUUUUCUUGCUUAUAGAGAUAUUCCAUGGGAUAGCAAAUCCUGUGUCAUGGAGAUGAAGUCAAAAUUCCUGAUUCCAAAAGGUUUUGAGAAAACAAAGAGGGGGAAUGACGUAAGAAAGAUAGGCAUGAGCAUGUGGUAACUAGGUUAGCACGUGUGCUUCCCAGCCCAGGAGCGACCAAAUACUGUGGUGGCGUCAGGUGUGCAGUGGAGAGGAAUAUAGAGGCUGUAUGGCCUCCCUCAGUGAGGGCAGGGCAAGAGGGAUCACUCUGAGAGAACAAAAAUAGGCCCCAAGUUGCUAAGCAGUGAUUGGGAACCUUCCUUUCCUUGGCGGAGAUGCAUGACAUUCCCUACCGAUCCCCAGACACAGCCUGUGGGACUCUUAGGAGAAAUGGUGAUUUACUGAAUAACUGACCCGUUGCCGAGAUGAGUACAAUGAAGUGGAGGUGAUGAACUCAAAUCGUCUUCCAGGGCCAGGCGGCUGACCGGGGUGAGCGUAGUGGCCCGCUGGGGACCAUGGCCGCCCUGACAGCCACACCCACCUGGAGCUGACUUGGUUCUGGCUGUUGCUGCCACUGUGAAAUCUGUAUCUCUCUCCAUCUCUGCUCUACUAUCCCCGGCCUUGCCAGACAGUGUUCUUUUUCGGAAGAAGUCUAGAUUUUUGCAUGAAAAAAACUCAAUCUUUAAAGGUCGACUCAGAACAUUUUAAGGAGGCCUCCACUUGGUCUGAUGCAGUCUUGCUAAUUAAGAACUAAAGGCCUUCUGACCUUCUUGGUGCUCAUGCUGUACGGCAUCUGAAUGUCUCGACCGAGUCUGAGCCGUGCAGCUGUCCUCCACCUGCGAAAGUAAUGAGAAUCCUAUCACGGGACAUAAGGAUAGGUCUAAACAGGGUCCAUGCCAAGAAAACAGUGGGGUGCUCUCCCAGGCCUCUCCCCUGUCCACUAACCCUGGCCUUGCCGGCUGCCUUCCAGGCUCUGGGGGAAGAGCUCCUGCAUUCUUCCCUGGCCACCUUGGCUCCAGGGCUCCCCAGAGAGCCUCUUCCCUCCCCAAGUACCUGAGAAAGAUGAGAGAGGCACGUGCUCUGCUGGGAAGGUCCAGUGAGCGGUUCAAGGGCCUGGAAUCUCCCUACGGCCAAGUCUAAGGGUUCUGGGAUUCUGGGCUUUGUGGGCUUUGCUUGCUUGCUGGGAAUGGGCUUUCCCUGUCCCGCCCUGCCCCACCUCGCCUCUGUCUCUCAGAAGCUCCAGAACCCAGCAGUGACCUGCAAAAUGUGGCCUCUGAUGGGGGCUUAGGGUGGGAGAUGGGGAGAGCCUACAUUGUCUUUUGCUCCUUGAAAACUUUAAUAGCUCCUAUUUUCCAGAGAAUGGUGCUUUGUGAGCAACAUGCGAGUAAGAGAGAAAUAGGAGGAAGGGGGAGUAGGGGCGGAUGGGAGAAGAGUGGCUCAUUUUUACCUCUCACUGCCUUGACAUUUUGUGAACGUGAAGCUUAAACUUUCUGGGCUUACAAGACCCAGGGGCACGUCAGCUCCUUAGAUGGGCUCAGCCUGACACAUAAUUCUUAAACCUUUCCUGUUUAAGAAACUUCUAGAGGCUGUGUACUCUCACCAAUCCUCUUCGAGAAUUUGUUCAUGUGUAUUUCCCCAUUAUAUGGAUGAGGCUCAGGAUAACAGCAUAGUGGCUACCUUCUACUGAGUUUUGAGGUGCUAAUAAGUAUGUUUGUCUGAGGCUGCACAUGUGGGUGGCUCUGUGUGUAUGAUCCAAGGGACAAAAUGACGAUGUAGGAACCAGCAAGAACGGAAUCUGGGCUGAUGCUUCAGUCUCCACCUGGGUGAUGGCUAGCCUCCCGCCCUCCACCACCGCAUCCCACACGUGCUGCGCACUGUCCCCGUGUCUCCUGGAGAACCAAACUGGAGAAAACCUUUCUGAGUAUCUCUCAUAGUACCCCUUCCUUAAGAAGAUGUGGUUUAGAGCAUGUGUGCAAUCCUGCCUCUGUAAUUAGGAAACGGAGCCCGAGGCUUUCCAUUGUUGGUUGAACCCAGGACAGCUGGUGCUAUUCACAGGCUGAAGAACUGGGCAGUUCUUACUUGGGUCUGUCCUAGGAUGUGGAGGAAGUUCAGGACUAACGCUAGGCAGAGAGUAUGACUCGGUUUACCCAGCCUAGGGGCCUCUGGAUGGGAACACUCCAUUCCAAGAUCUCAGCAGAGCAGGGCUUCCUGGCUUGAGGCUGGAAGCCUUUGGGAAGAGGCCCAGCUGGGACAUUCCCUGGGCACCUGUCUUCCGCUGAAGGGAGCAAGGUGCCCUCUGGGACUGACAGCCAUGACCCUCUGUGCCAUCCUCAAUCCUUGAGCCAUAUAUCAAGAGUCCUCUAGAGCCGGAUGGUCCUCAAAAGUCUGUCCAAGGAAUGCCAACGUUCACCGGGCUCUGAGAAACGACGCAAAUCUCUGAGCUGGGGACCACUUGGAGAACCGGCUUAGUAACAGUCCUGAUCUUCGCAAGCCAGCUUCUUCUGCAUCUGAGGGGCUCCUGGCGCCCAGAGGAGGCAGACAGAUGUCUUCUAGCUGAGUUUCUAACCGCAUGAUGAGACUCAGACCUUCCGCUGCACUAGAAAAUCUGCAACAGUGUCCCUGAGUCACUUCUCCUUAGUGGGCAGACUCGUGUUAGAUUUGUGGAACCCAGCUCUCUGAUUUACUCCUUUUGGAAAACCCAUGGAAUUUCAUGUAUAAGGCUUUCAUUUGUAUUUUAAGGUUUUUCUGUUUGUUUUGAGUAUAUACAUGGUGCUCAAUAGCAACAUCUUAGCAGAUGAAGCAGUUUAUGAUUCCACUCCCUCCUGUAUGACAGGUAGCCACUAUACUGAAUCAAGGUGCUGAACUCAAAUCACAAAAUUCUGGCUUACCGAUACAACAACCAAUACAUCUUUGUUCUGUAAUGUAAAAUUUGACUCCUUACUUUUAUAACUUAUUAAAGUUAAAAUGUCUGUGUUUUUGCAAAUCA